GCAGUCCACCGCCAGGAGCCUUCCGGUUUCUGCGCGGUGCGCGACCUCGUCCCGAAGCCUGGGGAUACACCCUCUCGAGAGCCCGCUGUCGCCCUCCGUUAAGGUCGAACCCCUCACAGUUGCUGUGGGCAACUCCAGCCCAACAUUCCCUCGCUCUGGUUCUCGCCCCAUUGGGAAACUCGGCCCCACGCUUCCCACUUUUCUGGAUGAGGUGUCCCCUUUCUCCCCACUAAAAUGUCAAAUAACCUACGGAGGGUCUUCCUGAAACCCGCAGAGGAAAAUUCAGGCAACGCCUCGCGUUGUGUUUCAGGCUGCAUGUACCAAGUAGUUCAGACGAUUGGCUCGGAUGGAAAAAAUCUUCUGCAAUUACUUCCAAUUCCUAAGUCUUCUGGAAAUCUUAUACCACUAGUUCAAUCUUCAGUCAUGUCUGAUGCUUUGAAAGGGAAUACAGGAAAACCAGUUCAAGUUACUUUUCAGACUCAGAUUUCCAGCUCUUCCACAAGUGCAUCAGUUCAAUUGCCCAUUUUUCAGCCAGCCAGUUCUUCAAACUAUUUUCUUACAAGAACAGUAGAUACAUCAGAAAAAGGUAGAGUUACUUCUGUGGGAACUGGAAAUUUUUCUUCAUCAGUUUCUAAAGUUCAGAGUCAUGGUGUGAAAAUUGAUGGACUCACCAUGCAAACAUUUGCUGUUCCUCCCUCAACACAAAAAGACUCAUCUUUUAUUGUAGUUAAUACCCAGAGUCUUCCAGUGACUGUGAAGUCUCCAGUUUUGCCUUCUGGGCAUCAUUUACAGAUUCCAGCCCAUGCUGAAGUGAAAUCUGUACCAGCGUCAUCAUUGCCUCCUUCAGUGCAGCAAAAGAUACUUGCAACUGCCACCACCAGUACCUCAGGAAUGGUUGAGGCCUCCCAAAUGCCAACCGUUAUUUAUGUAUCUCCUGUAAAUACAGUGAAAAAUGUAGUUACCAAGAACUUUCAAAACAUUUACCCAAAACCUGUUACAGAAAUAGCAAAGCCAGUAAUACUAAAUACCACACAAAUUCCAAAGAAUGUUGCUACAGAGACACAAUUGAAAGGUGGUCAGCAUUCUCAAGCUGCUCCAGUGAAAUGGAUUUUCCAAGAUAAUCUACAGCCUUUUACGCCAUCUCUUGUUCCUGUUAAGUCUUCAAAUAAUGUGGCUUCAAAGAUUUUAAAAACUUUUGUAGAUAGGAAAAAUUUGGGAGAUAAUACUAUAAAUAUGCCACCAUUGAGUACCAUCGAUCCUAGUGGGACGCGAUCCAAAAAUAUGCCUAUUAAAGAUAAUGCUUUGGUUAUGUUUAAUGGGAAAGUCUAUCUGUUGGCUAAAAAGGGGACAGAUGUUCUGCCAUCACAAAUUGACCAACAGAAUUCUGUUUCUCCUGAUACUCCAGUAAGAAAAGACACGUUACAGACAGUGAGUUCAAGUCCAGUCACAGAAAUAUCCAGAGAGGUUGUAAAUAUUGUUUUGGCUAAAAGUAAAUCUUCCCAGAUGGAGACAAAAUCACUUUCCAAUACCCAGCUUGCUUCCAUGGCCAAUCUAAGGGCAGAGAAGAAUAAAGUGGAGAAACCAUCUCCUUCUACCACAAAUCCACAUAUGAACCAAUCCAGUAACUACUUAAAACAGAGUAAGACUUUAUUCACAAAUCCAAUCUUUCCAGUUGGAUUUAGUACAGGACACAAUGCCCCCAGAAAAGUAACAGCCGUCAUUUAUGCUAGAAAAGGAAGUGUCCUCCAGAGCAUAGAGAAAAUAAGUUCCUCUGUUGAUGCAACAACUGUUACUUCACAACAGUGUGUUUUCAGAGACCAAGAACCAAAGAUCCAUAAUGAGAUGGCAUCAACAUCAGAUAAAGGUGCCCAAGGAAGAAAUGACAAGAAAGAUUCUCAAGGAAGAAGUAAUAAGGCAUUACAUCUGAAGAGUGAUGCUGAAUUUAAAAAGAUAUUUGGCCUUACUAAGGAUUUGAGAGUGUGCCUUACUCGAAUUCCUGACCAUUUGACCUCUGGAGAAGGUUUCGAUUCCUUUAGCAGUUUGGUAAAGAGUGGUACUUACAAAGAGACAGAGUUUAUGGUGAAGGAAGGAGAGAGAAAACAGGUCGCUGUUAGGGGAGAGGAUUUGGCGAUUUAUAGAAGAAGAGAGAAAUAAGGAAGAAGAAAAGAGGAGAGAAAAAGUGAAGAAAGACAAAUCCAGAUGAUCUUGGAAGCUCACUUCCUCCCAUGUGGGAGCUUAGCAAGAUACUAAUAACAGCUGAGGUGGGACAGGGACUCUUCUAAUAAGCUUACUUCGUAAAUCAGGAACAGUUACCUAAAACAGUUAGCACUGUUACAGAGUCAAGAGACCAGAGGUUCUCCGUCCUCCUAGGUAGAAAUAUGCAGAACUUUACAUACGGGGUCCCUCGGCUAGAGGCCUGUCCAUGGUGUCUGCAGGCUGGCUAUGCUCAGAUUAAGCAAGACUCUUUGUGGGAUAAGAAAAGCCACUUUGUUGGUAUUCCUAUCAAAAAUUUAAAUAACCUGAAUCUAAUCAUGAGGAAACAUCAGAUAAACCCAAAUGGAGAAACAUUCUAAAAAAGAACUGACCUUACUCUUCAAGAAUAUCAAUGGCAAGAAAAAUUCAGGAAGUGUUCCAGACUAAAGGAGACAAAAGUGACAGUUGAAGGCAAUGCGUGACUAGAAAUUUCCUUUUGCUAUAAAGAAUAUUAAAGAGGUAAUUGGUGGAAUCUGAAUAAAGUACAUAGAUUGUUAAUUAUAUUGCAUAAGUGUUAAUUUCCUGGUUUUGAUCAUUGUAAAGUAGUUAUAUAAGAGAAUGCAUUUGUUUGUAGAAAUAUACACUAACAUUCUUAGGGGAAAGGGCAUCAAUCAAAUUACUAAUUACUGUCAAAUGAGAGAGCCAGAGAAUAAACAAAUGAAGUAAAAUGUUAAUAUUUUGGAAAUCUGGGUGAAAAGGAUUUAGAAAUUUUUCAUAAUAUUUUUUCAACCUUUUUAUCAGUCUGAAUUUUGUCAUUUUUUUAAAGGGAUGGGAAAUAAAUAAAUGAUCUAAGGGAUUCUCAUCUCAAAAUCAUUACAAUUUGUCUUCUAUGUUAUAAAUACUGAGAUUCUACAAUAGUUAUUUUAAGAAGACUAAACUAUGGAAUAAUUCUUGAAUGCCUUUAUUUGCUCCUGAUAUAAGGUAAGCCAUAAGUUCAAAUUUACUUUAACAAGUAAACUUUAACAAGUUUUAAAAGAUAUGAGGCAUUAAAAUCAUUUCUUACCCCUAUUCCUCAAUCUAGUUCUCCUGAAAUAGAAAAGGCCAAACAAAAAGGUUUGGAAAAUAAAAUAUAUGUUAAGUAUUUAGUUUGCUAGCAUAGUAGCUUAAGAUCAAUUACAUUUACAAUUAAGUGGUAUUUUUAUGUUUGCUUAUGUUAAAAUGCACUAGGAAUUUAUGUAAAUGAAGAAUACAGUCUAAUGAUGCUUACUUAAUAAAAAAUCUCUUAGAAAAGGGACUAUAGUAUAAUGUAGAAGAAAGAGCAUGCCAUAGAGAAUCAGAAGACAUUCUGAAUAACUAUUAAGUAAUUUUAUGAUUUUUGGACAAGUCAUUUUACCUGAAAAGUAAGCAGAUUGGACAGUUGCGACAGCUCCUAUUUAUUGGCUCUCAUUGUGAGUUAAGAUACUUUAUUUGAAUCUAAAUAAUCUCUAACUUCGCUUGAAGUACCAAUAUUCUAAUUCUUGGAAUAUAGCACUCUCAUUUUAAAUGAUUAUAAAAAUGUAUGCUUGUGUCAUAUUUUCUUUUACAAUAAUUCUUGGUCAGAGCUAUGACAUAUUGAUGCUAUUGCUUGGGUAGAAAUUCUGCUGUGUGCUUAUGAAAUGGAUAAUGAAGAGAGAGCACUCACCUCUAACUCUCAGUAUAGAGAUUCCUGGCCUUUACUCUGAGUGGUCAUCCACUGGCUUUGCAAAUGCAUGUCUUUCUCUUUCCCAAAACCUACCUCCAGACAGCCUUCUCAAACUGACCACCCAACCUCCAGCUCAAUCCUUCCCUCCUCUGCCCCAGCAGCCAUGCUGGAGUCCUGCUCUGCAUAGCUGUCUGUUUUCUCUGGGUUACUUUGCUUCAGUGCCCUGCACCUGCAGUGGCAGAUGGGUCCUAGGAGCUUCCUGAGGACAGGUGCCCAGUCUCUAGGGCCCAGGGUGAUCUACACACAGUGGAUGCUUGCUUGGUACAAGAAGUGCCCUAGGCUGACUAAUCUAGGGACGCAGAACAAACCACUAUAACUGAAUCAAUGCAGUACUUCCUGGAACAGAAGCUAAGCUGAAAACAAUGGCUGUAACCUCACAAGAAGCUCCACCCUUCCUUCUGCUCUAAGUGAAAAUCUAGGUUGAGGAGGCAAAAACCUGCCUCUUCUCCCUCAUUUCAAACCCACAUCCCAUCAAUUCUGUCGUGUGAACAUGGUGGGCAUAGCCCCACCCAGAGCUGGACCUAGGACCUGCCUGGUGAGCGAUCUUGCCCUCCACUUUCUGGUGCCAAGUAGGAGAAAGGGCUUUCCACUUCAUGUGGCUCUGUAAACAUGGUGUGUUACACUGCAGUCUCACUUGCUUUCUCUCAUUUCUAACAUGCCUGGAGGUACACACUUCUUUGAAUUUGAAUAUACAGCACCCUUGGUCUAGAAUGUCUCCAUAGCAAACCCAUACUUCUGUGAAAGUGAACCCACCAGUCACCUCUCUAGGCAGUUUUUGGCACACUCCUAACUCCUACAGUUUGUGCACGUUCUCCAUCUAUUAUAGAAAAGAGCACAUUGCACUGUAUUUGUAUAUUGCUGUGACUGUCAUCCAUAAUAAACUCUACAACUCCUUUCA